GCUAUGACGCCCAGGUCUCCGUAGGCACCUGCAGCUAGCAGCUGAGCGCGUAGGGGCCGAGCGACCCCGGGACGCUCGCGGCACCCUCCGCAGGAAAAUUUCCGACUUGGUUCUUGAGGUUCCUGCCUCAGCCCCAAGGAGGAAAGCACCCAUUCUCCCCUCUUUUCCGCAUUACGGGCCUUUUCUGCUUCUCCCCAGUAUGGUCCGAAACUACAGGAGGGGAACCCCUCCUGGCCCGGCCUUUCUAUUCCCUGGCUGGAGUGAUUCCGCCUGAAGGAGAAUUCGCCCGUUUUCCCCGGACCCAGCUGCCACAAGCAUUUAGUAUUAGGCUGCCGCUUAUUAUUAGAGCGGGCUUAGAACAUCCUCAGCGAGGGAAAAGUUCAGUUAGAAGACAUACUUCACCAUCUUGAAAAAGAAGAAAUCAAUCCCCUUGCUACUACAGAAGAACAACUCUGUUUGGUGCUUAUUCCAGCCAGCACAGUGAAGACAGGCUGAGGACUGCUACCACAGAUGUAGAAGAGCUUAUAGUGAAGCACAUGGGUGAAACAAAAGAAGUUGGAGUGCUGGAGUGCAGUAGCAUGAUCUCCGUUCACUGCAGCCUCAACCUCCUGGGCUCAAGUAAUCCUCCUGUCUUGUCCUCCCAAAAUGCUGGAAUUACAGUAUCAUAAUGAAGACCUGGAAAAAGACAAAACAUCACAAAACUGCCUAGGAAGAGGAAUGGAACAAGUAGCAAAGAAGUUAGGGGUGGCUCAUGAAGAGAUUCAAAGGCUCACUGAUGAACUACAAGUGAAGGAGAAGGAACAAUGUAAAUUAGAUUCUGCACUUAAGAAGGCUCAACUAGAAAUUGACAAAUUGAAGGAAAAUUUGGUAAAGCUGAAAGAAAAUGAUGCAGCUGACCUACAGAAAGCAAAGGAACAAAAUCAGAGACUGGAUGAGGAAAUUCUGGCUUUAAGAAAUAGGGUUCGAUCACUUGACUCAGAAAAAAAGGUGCUUGGUGAAAUGGUUGAAAGACUUAAAGGAGAGGUGUGUGAAUCUCAAGAGAAUAAGCAACUUGGAAACCACUCCCCUGGAAAAACUGUGGGUGGUGAACAGAGAGAACAGAUUGAGGCUUCCAUGUUAGAGCCUGAAUUAUCAGUAACAUAGGAAGAUAGAAGAGAAACCAGUACAAAAGAUCAAGAGACAAAGUACAAGAUUUGAAUGAGAUCCUGAAAAUGAGCCAAGAAAAAAAUGAAAUGUUUGAAAGUGAGUGGUCAAAAGAGAGAGAGAGAGAGAAGCAGUUGGCAUCUGGUCUUGACACUGCAGAGAAGGCCUUGAAAGUUGAAAGUGAGGUCUUGAAGCUUUCACAAGAAUUUGCACAAUUAAAUCAUUUUACUCUAGGGGGAAAAACUGCACCUUCUAAUUUAAUUACAAGUGAAAAUACCUGUAAAGAUCCUGAAUCUAAUGAACCAAUUUUGGAAACAGAAAUUCAAAGCCGAAAGGAAGAGACAGAGGAACUCUGUCCCAAAUUAGGAGAAAGAAAGCAGAAGGAAAUUCCAGAGGAGUCAGUAAAGGAGGGCAGUUUUCCAAGAGAGGGGCAGAAGGAGGAGGGCUCACAACAGAAUCGAGAUAUGAAAGAUGAAGAAAAAGAACAGCAGUUAACCAUGAAGCCUGAGGAAAUUGUGAGGCUUAGAGAAGAGCUGAGCCAUAUAAAUCAGAGCCUUCUUCAGUCUCAGAGCUCUGGGGAUAGUUCAGAUGACAGUGGUGCCCAGAGUGACUGAACUGGAAAAUGUAGAUGAGAAGAACUACUGUUCUGGUUUUUCCAUCCUUCAAAAGAAGCUAAAACUUUUGGGCCUUUGUCCUCUUGGUAAAACUGGGGUGCAUCUCUUGUAUACAGUAUCUCUGUUUUGCAUCCAUCAUCUGGAGAAAAACUAAAAUACAACCAGCAAGGGGAAGUACAACAACUUCACCAGAAUUUGCACCGGCUCCAGAUUCUAUGCAACUCAGCUGAAAAUGAGCUUCGAUAUGAACGAGGGCAGAACUUGGACUUAAAGCAACAUAAUAGCUUACUUCAGGAAGAAAACAUUAAGAUAAAGAUUGAACUAAAGCAUGCCCAACAGAAGUUAUUAGACAGCACAAAGAUGUGCUCUUCACUCACGGCAGAGUACAAGCACUGUCAGCAGAAAAUCAAGGAACUGGAGUUGGAAGUACUUAAACACACUCAGAGCAUUAAAUCACAGAACAACCUACAGGAAAAGCUGGUUCAGGAGAAAUCUAAAGUUGCUGAUGCAGAGGAAAAGAUUUUGGACCUGCAGCGGAAAUUAGAACAUGCUCAUAAAGUCUGUCUCACAGACACUUGUAUUUCAGAGAAGCAGCAGCUAGAGGAAAAGAUAAAAGAAGCAACACAAAAUGAAGCUAAAGUAAAGCAACAAUAUCAAGAAGAACAACAGAAGAGGAAACUUCUAUAUCAGAACGUAGAUGAGUUACACAGGCAAGUGAGAACCUUACAAGAUAAAGAAAAUCUACUGGAAAUGACCUGUUCUCAGCAACAAUCCAGAAUUCAGCAACAAGAGGCCCUACUUAAACAACUGGAAAAUGAAAAAAGAAAAUAUGAUGAGCAUGUCAAAAGCAACCAGGAAUUGUCAGAGAAGCUAUCUAAGCUACAGCAAGAGAAGGAAGCUCUACGUGAAGAAUAUUUGCGAUUAUUGAAGCUGCUUAAUGUCCAUGUGAGAAACUAUAAUGAGAAACAUCACCAACAAAAAGUCAAGCUUCAAAAAGUCAAGUAUCGUUUAACUAAUGAAGUAGAACUACGAGAUAAGAGAAUUAACCAAUUUGAAGAUGAAAUUGGAAUCCUGCAACAUAAAAUAGAAAAGGAGAAGGCAAUACAGGACCAGAUCACUGCCCAAAAUGAUACCCUGCUUCUAGAAAAAAGGAAACUUCAGGAGCAAGUCAUAGAGCAAGAACAGUUGAUCCACAGCAACAAAUGGACGAUAUCUUCCAUCCAGAGCAGGGUACUUUACAUGGAUAAAGAAAAUAAGCAAUUACAGGAAAAUAGUCUUCGUCUCACACAGCAGAUUGGCUUCUUAGAGCGAAUUAUAAGGAGCAUCCAUAUUCGCAGAGGAGAGAAUCUUAAGGAGUUUCCUGUUCCAAAAUGGUGGCAUAGAGGCAAGCUGGCUUCUCUCCCUCCAACAAAGAAACAGAAAGAAAUAUACAGCACUGAGGUCUUCACCAGCAACAAUGCAGAACUCCAGCAUGAGGAUGAGUCAGUUCCUGAGGCCACAGAGAAGUGGAAACACUCUGAGCAGAUGGAAACAACAAUUAGUGACAUCCUUGAAUCCGAAGUAGUGAAUGAAAUAUUGCCUUUAUCAAACUCCAGUUUUUCAGGAAAAGGUUUGGUAGAGUCAUUUGCAAGUCUUCAAGAGACUGAAGAGAUCAAGUCAAAAGAAGCAAUGGCAAGUUCAAAGUCCCCUGAAAAGUCUCCUGAGAAUCUUGUGUGUUCACAGAAUUCUGAGGCUGGAUACAUAAAUGUGGCUUCUCUGAAGGAGACACAUGGUAUACAAGAACAAGACCAAAAGUCAGAACUAUAAAAUCACUGGUGCCUAAAGCUAUACUGAACAAAAGUGGUAAUUUAAAGCCUGGACAAAAGGUGGACCAUGACAUUGAGAAGAGUUACCACAGAUCCCAAAUGGAUAUCACCCAAGAGUCUUCAAAACUGCUGAUAAAUUCAUUAAAGCAGUUGUAAAAAUGGAUUUCUCAAGUUUGUUUGAUAUCCUCAGAUGCCUUGUAUUGACCAAAAUAUUGACUUUAGUUCAAUGAUUUAUUUAGGUUUCUCUUCAGCAGAGCACAUGUAGGGUUAAUUCAACAUUCUUUCCCAUUAUCAUGGGUAUCUUUUCUGAUUUAUUUUUUAACAGUAAAAACAAUACAGUCACAUUAAAGCAAAUUUUGUUUUUAAAAAAACCCUCCUAUGCUGGGCGUGGUGGCUCACGCCUAUAAUCCCAGCACUUUGGGAGGCUGAGGUGGGUGGAUCACGAGGUCAGGAGAUCGAGACCAUCCUGGCUAACACGGUGAAACCCUGUCUCUACUAAAAAUACAAAAAAAUUAACCGAGUGUGGUGGCGGGUGCCUGUAGUCCCAGCUACUCAGAAGGCUGAGGCAGGAGAAUGGCGUGAACCUGCGAUAGCACCACUGCACUCCAGCCUGGGUGACAGAGUGAGACUCCGUCUCAAAAAAAGCAAAAAACAAAAACAAAAACCCUCCUAUAAUACCAUAAGCUUUUUUUUUUUUUUUUGAGACGGAGUCUCUUACUCUGUCACCCAGGCUGAAGUGCAGUGGCAUGAUCUCCGCUCACUGCAACCUCUGCCUCCCAGGUUCAACCAAUUCUCCUGCCUCAGCCUCCCAAGUAGCUGGGAUUAUAGGUGCCCGCCACCAUGCCCAGCUAAUUUUUGUAUUUUUAGUAGAGACAAGGUUUCACCAUGUUGGCCAUGCUGGUCUUGAACUCCUGACCUCAGGUGAUCCACCCACCUCAGCCUCCCAAAGUGCUGGGAUUACACCAAUACCACAGUCUUAACACAACUAAUUUUAUUUUACAGUUAUUCCCUUUUGGUCCUAAUUCAAGUACAUAUAUUCUAAGUGGUUAUUAUAAUAUUGUAUAUUCAUUUUCACAGUUUGAUUUUUAAUUUACUGUAUAUACCAUGGAAACAUUUUCAAUCGCCAUAUGAUAUUCAAUCAUGUUGAUGUUCUAUAAUUAUUUUUAUGGGAAAAGUUUUAAAUGUUUAAUGAAGAAGAUUUAGAGCAAUACAUUAUUUAAAAGUGGAUAGGAGGUUGGGCGUGGUGGCUUACACCUGUGAUCCCAGCACUUUGGGAGGCCGAGGUGGGCAGAUCACCUGAGGUCAGGAGUUCGAGACCAGCUUGGCCAACUUAGGGAAACCCCGUCUCUAACAAAAAUACAAAAACAAUUAGCCAGGUGUGGUAGUGCGCGCGCCUGUAGUCCCAGCUACUGGGGAGGCUGAGGCAGGAGAAUCACUUGAACCCGAGAGGCAGAGGUUGCAGUGAGCCGAGACUGCACCAGUGCACUCCAGCCUGGGUGACAGAGCAAGACUCCAUCUCGAAAAAAUAAAUAAAAUAAAAUAAAAUAAAAGUGGAUAGGAAAAUACCAAGAGCUUUUCCUGGGGGAGGGGGUAUGAGAAGAGAGUUCACAUAAACCCCAUUACACAGAAACUACCCCUAAAUAUUUCCAAACAGGAGUACAAAGUAGGUGAACAGUCUCCAGCUCAUCUUUAGUGUAGUGGGACUGCUUCUUCAGAAAAGAUCAGCAACAUUCACAUCCAUUUCAUCUAUCAGGGUGGAACAGUACUGCUCAGUAUCUCUGAGGAUGUGGAUGUUCUAUAAAUUAAACGUUCUCUUGUUUGGCAUUUAAGCUGUUUUUACUUUUUUUUUUUUUUUUUUUUUUUUGAGACAGGGUCUCACUUUGUAACCCAGGCUGGAGUGCAGUGGUUUGAUUACUGCUCAUGCAGCCUCAACCUCCCAUGCUUAAGUGAUCCUCUCUCCUCAGCCUCUCCCAAGUACAGGCAUGUGCUACCAUGCCUGGCUCAUUUUUGUACUUUUUGUAAAGACGAGGUCUCACUCUCACUCUAUUGUUCAAGCUGGUCUCAAAUUUCUGGGCUCAAGUGAUCCUCCCACCUAAGCCUCCUAGGUGAUAGGAUUAUAGGAUGAGCCUCUAUGCCAGGCCUGGUUUUACUUUGUUACUAUUUAAGAUUAUGCUGUGUUGAAGGUCUUUGUGCAUGUAGUUCUUUUCUUCUUUUGAAUUACUCCAGAAAACAAAUUCGCAAGAUUGGACUGAGUCAAAGGAUAUAAAUGUUAAUAUUGCUCUAGGACAUCACUUCCUUUGCUUUAAAAAAGGGUUCUGCCUGACCAGGUGCGGUGGCUCACGCCUAUAAUCCCAGCAUUUUGGGAGGCCGAGGCAGGUGGAUCACUUGAGGCCAGGAGUUCAAGACCAGCCAGGCCAACAUGGCAAAGCCCUGUCUCUACUAAAAAUACAAAAAUUAGCCGGGUAUGGUGGUGCACACCUGUAGUCCCUGCUAUGCGGGAGGCUGAGGCUCGAGAAUCACCUGAACCCAAGAGGUAGAAGUUUCAGUGAGCUGAGACCACUCCACUGUACUCCAGCCUGGGCAAAAAGUGAGACUCUGUCUCAAAAAAUAAUAAUAAUAAAUACAUAAAUAAUAAAAUAAAUAAAAAGUGUGUCAACAUACUGUUUUCAUAGUCAAGUUACUCAACCUCCUUGAGCCUCAAUUUCUUGAUUCCUAAAAUGGGAACAAUAAUAGUUCUCUAUCCCAUAGGGUUGUGAGGACCAAAUGAAAUGAAGCAUGUAAAGUAUUUAGCACGUAGUAACUGCUUAAUAAAUGCUAUCAUCAUUUAUUUUCACUAGAGGUUUAUCAAUGUACUAUUUUUUUCACAACCUCAUCAACAUUGGAUAUUAUCAAUUUUAAAGAUUUAUUCUAAAACAGUUGGUAUAAAAUUAUACUGAAGCGUGACUGCUGCUGUUCCUUUUCCCCCUCCUCCCCUUUCUUCUUUUUCAGUUGGAGGAGACCAAGAGGAGAGGAUCAGUAACCAGAAAUAAAAAUGACCCUUUACAUUGAGACACACUGUAUUUUUAUAUGUAAUCCUUGCUUUCUCAGACAACAGAGCUAGAAAGAUGAUCAUAGGAACUAGGAAAUAAUAACUAUUUUAUUAAAUGCAUGCUGUUAUAUUGAA